UGCUGGGAUUACAGGCGUGAACCACCAUGCCCGGCUUAUUUGGUUUUUAUAGUAACGCUAUUGAUUCCAUUUUUACCAAGGAACUGAGAUACAGAGAGAUUUAGUAACUUGCCCAAGGUGACAUAACUAGUAAAUGGUGGGGGUAGGUUCAAAAUCAGGCAGUUUGCUAUUUCUUAUUUAAAGCCACAAUUCAUGAGAAUUGAGCCAUUCUCAAAUGUACAGGUUAUUCUUGUAAAUUGGAGACUAUUGUAUCAGUGUUACAAAUGACCUAUUGUAAUCUCCCAUCCAAGAACUAACCAUUUCUGACCCUGCUUAGUGUCAAUAGUCAGGUGCAUUCAGGGUGGUGUGGCUGGAGAUGAUCUUAUAUGAUCUGAGCCCCUUGCUUCAUGAACAAUAUUUUCAGUUACUUUACACAGUAAGCACGUACUUAAACAAUUAUUUGGCUGGGCGCAGUGGCUCAUGCCUGUAAUCCCAGUACUUUGGGAGGCUGAGAUGGGAGGCUCACUUGAGGUUAGGAGUUCGAGACCAGCCUGGCCAACAUGGUGAAACCCUGUCUCUACUAAAAAUACAAAAAUUAGCUGUGCAUGGUGGCAUACGCCUGUAGUCCCAGCUACCUGGGGGUUGAAGCAGGAAAACUGCUUGAACCUGGGAGGCGGAGGUUGCGGUGAGCUGAGAUCAUGCCACUGCACUCCAGCCUGGAUGACAGAGUGAGACUCCGUCUCAAAUAAACAAACAAACAAAAACCCCACCAAACCAAAAAACCCAAUUAUUUUAAUUAUAAAUCUGAACUGCAUUAAAAGAUAGUAAAUUUAGCUAGUCAACUUGAAUAACUUUUAACAGAGAGUUAGUUGUCUCUUCUGUUUCCUUAGGGAAGAAAGAUGAGUUCCUUCAGUUCCCAAAUGAGUCCUCAAUUCAACAUGAGUGAUUUCACCAGAAUAAAAUCUUCUUACUUCUGCAAAAAGCAGCUAAUGCUUUCGGAAGCUAAAUAAUCCCAAUGUGUGACUCCUGCCAGUUUCUUUUCUUUGAAACCUCAGCAGCAGCAUAACUAGUGAUUCACCCUUCUUGAAAUGAAUGCUGUGAUUCGCGUUAUGCACAGAUGGCUACUGAAUGCCCAGGUCACAGCCUUUGCGUCUGGCCUUGACUCGUUAAUAAGAACAGGAACUGGGCAUGGUGUAUUGCACAGUGAUUAAGGGCUUAAAGCUAAGAGCAGUGCCUGGCCCCAAGUAAGACAUGAGUAGAACUUUGCUGCUGCUAUUUUUGCUGUUGUAUAUUGGGCUCUACCUUGUGCUGGGCACUACGUUAAGCACGCUAUGUGCAUUGCCUAAUUGAAUUCUCAUCACAUUCCCAUGAAGUAGUUGAUGGUUUUGUUUUUAUCUUCAUUUUCAAAUGUAGAAACUGAAGCUUAAGGUUAUGACAUUUGCCCAAGACCAUGCAGCUGGUAAGUGGUUAGCGCCAUGGUACGAACCAAGUUAAAAAACAUUUUUUUUAAUUCAUAAAUUAUAAUGUACAGAAUCUUCUAGAAGCUUUCUUGUGCCUCCUCCUGAUUGUUAUUUUUCAACAAAGUUGCCUACUAUUCUAUCACCACAGAAAAGCUUUGACUGUUCUUGAACUUCAUAAAAACAGAAUCAUAUUCAUACAGUAUGUACUCUUUGUAUUUGGCUUUUUUUACUUAGUAUUAUGUUUGUGAAAUUCAUCCAUUGAUGUGAAAUACAUGGAUUUGCAUGUAGCGAUAAUUUGUUUUUCCUCAUUGCUAAAUAUAUUGCUACAUUUCUUAUUGUAUAGUUUAAUGUACAAAUAUGCCUCACUGUUGAUCUCUUCUACUGUUGAUGGACUUUGGUUGUUUUUAGUUCUUGGUUGUUAUUUAUUGUGCUACUUACUUUCUUUCUUUGUUUUUUUUUUUUUUUUUGGAAACAGUCUCCUCUGUUGCCCAGGCUGGAGUACAGUGAUGUGAUCUCAGCUCACUGCAACCUCCACCUCUGGGUUCAGGUGAUUCUUCUGCCUCAGCCUCCCAAGUAGCUGGGGCUACAGGUGCAUGCCACCAUGCCUGGCUAAUUUUUAAUUUUUAAAAGAGACAGGGUUUCGCCAUGUUGGCCAGGCUGGUCUUGAGCUCCUAACCUCAAGUGAUCUUCCUGCCUUGGCCUCCCAAAGUGCUGGGAUUAUAGGUGUGAGCCACCAUGCCUGGCCUAAUUGUGUUCAUUCUUGUACAUGAUUUGUAUACGUAUACGGCUCUUUGAGUACAUUUCUAGGUCAGCACUGCUGGGUCUUAAUAGGUGUGGAGCUGUAUUCUAUACUGUGAAACUGUUUUCUACACUCCCACCUAGCAGAGGGUUCAGUGGUUCUGUCCUAACACUGUAAUGACUAUCAUCAUUCUGGUGGGUGUGUAGUAGAAUCCAUAUCAAACUUGAUAUGGAUUUUGACUCCAUAGCCUAUGGACUUACCUGGUAAGAACAAUUUUAACAAUUAUAGCGCUCUUGCUAUACGGAAGGUGUUGUGCUGAUAUGUAAUAAUGAAUAUAACUUGAUUUCUGCCCUCUAGGAGUUUAUAGUCCAGUGGAAGAGAAAGACUCAGAAAUCACAUAAUCAUAGUCCAACACAGAAUCCAUGCAUAGGGCACUGUUGGAGCACUGGGAGAGUCUACUUCAAUCUGUGGGUUCAGGACGGGGUCGCUAAAGUCUUGCAGAAAGAAGUCAGUCUUCUGGGAUAUGGCUUCUUCGGGAAGGUGACAUUUAACCUGAGGCUGGGGGGGAUGAAAAUAGAGUCAUGUGAAGAGGAAUGGAUCAGAAGCCUGUGUAGCCACAGGGAGGAAGUGAACAGGUGAUGGUAGGCUGAGGUCAAAGAGCCCUGGAGUCCAUGGCAUUUGUAAACCAUUGCUGGCCUUGAAGUAGAGAGCCAAUGUUGCUAUGAAGCAGUCAAAACGGUUCUCCUUCAUCAGCCUGUGACCCACAGGGGACCCGCAGGCCUUUGUGGAGGCUGCCUCCAUUUGGCGGAGUGGUGGUGUUGGAGAAAAUGGCCUUACUGACUCCUGAACUAGGAAGCUCCUGAUCCUAACUCUCUUAGUAUCUCAUCUUGCGAAUUACUAAGACAGGGUCUUUAAGAUGUCUUAUUUAUUUUUUGAUGUACAUUUUGUAAAUUAAUUUUUAUAAUGCUUCAAAAGCUAAUUUUUAAAUUAUAAAAGUAAUAGAAUCACAUUACAGAAGCCAGAAAAUGGAGAAAAAACCCCCACUAUCAUUUUAUUAUAUAGUUUUUCCCAUCGUUUUAAUUGUAGGGUAUAGAUUAUUUUAUGUUAUCCCCGUGUCCUUUGACAUGUGACGAGCCUUUUUUCUUGAUUAUGUAGUCUUCAUUACUAUUUUAUUAUUGUAGAAUAUGAAGUGGAACACCUUGUACCACUUAAAUUUCCUCUUUUUUUUUUUUUGGAGAUGGAGUCUCUCUCUGUCGCCCAUGCUGGAGUGCAGUGGUGUGAUCUCAGCUCACUGCAAUCUCCACCUCCUGGGUUCAAGCCAUUCUCCUGUCUCAGCCUCCCGAGUAGCUGGGAUUAUAGGUGCGUGCCACCACACCAUGCUAAUUUUUGUAUUUUCAGUAGAGAUGGGGUUUCUUCAUGUUGGUCAGGCUGGUCUUGAACUCCUGACCUCGAGAUGCGCCUGCCUCAGCUUCCCAAAGUGCUGGGAUUACAGGCGUGAGCCACCAUACCCAGCACCAUUUAAAUUUCAAUCUUUCUUUCACUUUUAAUUGUAAUGAGAAAAAACCAAUAGAUGCUUAUUGUAAAGCAUUUGGAAAAUACAGAAAAGUAUAAGAUGAAAAUUAAAAACUUUUCAGUUCUACCAUGAAGAUAAACACAUGUUAAUAUUUGGGUAUAUUUCUUUUUUCCCCUCUGCUUUUAUUUACAUAUAUGUAUGCUUUUCUUUCCUUUUUUGUUUUUUUGAAUACAAAUUGGGGUUUUUUUUCCUGCAAGCAAGAUACUGUUAAUGGGGAUUUUGGAUGGCCAUAUAAUGAAAUAGGAAAACGAUUAAUGGAAGCCCAGGAGGAAAGACUUGGUGUUAUUAUAGGUUUGUAUCAUAUCACCAUUUUCCUGUUCUAUUUGGAGGAAGAGGGAAAGGGGAAAGGAAGCCAGCCCUUAUUGUGUGCCUGCCACGCACCUGGUCCUGCAGUGCUGGGAAGCACUGUGAGCUCUGACUCCCAGAAAAGUAGACGCUGGCACUGUGGGAAAGUGGGACCCUCAUGGCAGCGUGUUGUUUGAAAAACCAGUCUUUCAAACAUAAUAACUGAGCAUGUUGGAAAACCAGGCUGGCGUCAUGGUGUAAAUUGAGUUUACUCAAACCGGCAGGUUGUUGGGAAGGUACACAUACCUCUAUUGUUUUAACCCACUUGAAGAUUAAAAUGUGGGAAGAGCAUUUUGAAUAGAGAACACCGUACUUUAUCAUUUGGUGCAGAGGCCUUGUAUUUUUAACAAAAAUUGCCCCAAAGUUUCCUCCAAAUGCAUUAAAUCCAUGUUUUUGUUGUUUAACCAUGAAUAUUUUGAAAAAAUUUAUUAUUUUGAAAAUCCAGGCCCUUUAAAUUUUAUUUUUGCUCUCACAAAUCCUUCUUUCCUUUUGAGUUGGCACAUAAUUGUACAUACUUAUGAGAAAACAAAGUGAUAUUUUGAUACAUGUAUACAAUGUGUGAUGAACAUUAAUAGAGGAUUGGCUAAAUUAUGAUAUAUAUAAAGUGCUCAGAGAGGUGGAGGAGGUAAUAAGAUAGAAGGUGGACUUUUUAGGGAAGUCCUUUAGAGUAAUUAGUAUAUUCAUCACCUCAAACAUUUGUCAGUCCUUUGCAUUGUGAACAUUUGAAAUCCUAUCUUCUAGCUAUCUGAAAAUGUACAAUAAAUUAACUUAUUUCUCCUAUCUAGCUGUAACUUUGACCUGUUCACCAACUUCUUUCUAUCCUACCCUCUUCUCUACCUUUCCUAGCCUCUAAUAACCAUGAUUCCACUCUCUACUUCUUCAAUAUUUAAUUUAAUCCCCAAAUUCUAAUUGUAGUCCAUAUUUGAAUACUUCAUAUUAUUGGUCACAAUUUUGGGCUUUGUAUUAUUGGUCACAAUUUUGGUUGAUUAUUUUUUGAAAAGUAGAAUCUUGUUUUUUGAAGCCAGGCUUAAUCACCUGAAGACCCAGGACAUCUAUAGUUGUUUUUUUUUUUUUUCCUAACAAAAUUCUGUAUGCGGAAAAUAGGAAAAAUAAUACAAGAAAGACACAAGAAAUGGACAGUGCUACAUUUCUGAUUUUACAUCUUCAUGACAAUGAGUAAAGAUCUCUGAGUUUUGUCUUCGGAGCGGAGUAUGGAAUCUGUCCAUUGAGGAUUGCAGGUCGAGUGCAGGGGCUCAUGCCUGUAAUCCUAGCACUCUGGGCGGGGAGCCUCCAGCACUGAGGCUGGAGGAUUGCUUCAGCCCAGGAGUUUGAGACCAGCCUGGGCAACAUGGUGAGACCCCAUCUCCAUGAAAACUUAGACACUAAAUAAAACUCACUAUUUUCAUUCUUAUUAAUCUUAUUUAUUACUUGGAGAUAUCCUUAGAGGCUCUAGGUGUGUAAGUCUCCUUGUUCCUACCCUAAAUAGCUAUAGAAAUUGCUGUAUUUCUAAUACCUUUUUUUUUUUUUUUAAUGGGGUCUCACUGUGUCACCAAAGUGGUGGUGCAGUGGCAUAAUCAAAGCUCACUGCAGCUUCAAACUCCUGGGCUCAAGUGAUCUUCCUACCUAAGCCUCUCGAGUAGUUGGGAGUAGAGAUGUGCACCAUCAUGCCUAGCCAAGUUUUAAAUUUUUUUGUUUGUAGAGAUGGGGGUCUUGCUAUGUUGGCCAGGCUGGUCUUGAACUCCUGACCUCAGGCCCGCCUCGGCCUCCCAAAGUGCUGGGAUUAUAGGCGUGAGCCAUUGCACCCAGCCUCUUCUCAUUCUUAGGUCUGCCUUUUGUGGUUCUUCUGUCACUUUCUGUAACUGAUACUGUUAGCAGCUUAUGCUUUUGUUGCUUCUACUUGGCUUUGGGCUAAGGAUUGUAACUUCCAUCUGUGUCAAGUUGUGUGUGAAGGAGGCUGAGUUUGAAUUGUGUUUUAUGCUGGGUGCUGUGCUUGAGGCAGCUUGUUGCCUAAAAAGAAAAUGGUGGGCUUCACAGCACACACAGCUUUGGAUGCUCAAAGCCCAUUUGAGCUUCCAUUCACUUAUUUUCUUUCUUAUUGUAAAAACAAUACAUGUUUGUGCGGGCAUGGUGGCUCAUGCCUGUAAUCUCAGCAUUUUGGGAGGCCAAGGCGGGCGGAUCAUCUGAGGUCGGGAGUUGGAGACCAGCCUGGCUAACCUGGUGAAACCCUGUCUCUACUAAAAAUACAAAAUUUAGCUAGGCUUGGUGGCGCCUGCCUGUAAUCCCAGUUACUUGGGAGGCUGAGGCAGGAGAAUCGCCUGAACCUAGGAGGUAGAGUUUGCAGUGAGCCAGGAUUGCACCGUUGCACUCCAGCCUAGGCGACAGAAUGAGACCCUGUCUCAAAUUAAAAAAAAAAAAAAAAAAAAAAAAGGCAUGUUUGCAAUGAAAAUUGAAGCAUUACAAAAAUGUGUUAUUUAAAUGAAAGGUACCCUGUUUUAUCAUCUCUAGUCAUAACUACGCUUUAAGGAUUUGAUAAUUUUUUUUUAGAUUUUUCUGUAACUUUAUAUUUUUUACAGAGAUGGGGUUACUCUAUGUUAUUUUGGUACUGAUUUUUGUAUUUUUAAAAAUAUAUUUGUAUACUUUCUAUGGCUGUGUAUAUAAAUUUUUGUUGGUUGUUUUUAAUAGCUUCCUGGUGUUCCUUGGUAUAGAUAUAUCGUAAUUUAGCCAAUCUUCUAUUAAUGGAUAUUUGGACUAUUAUAAAUACCUCAUAUAUAAGUAUUUGUACUCUCUGAAGUGUUUGUAUAAUUCUUCUGUUCAGAGUUAAUUACUGGAAAUAGGGUUGGACGGUGUAUACAUUGAGCCAGUGCGCCCAGCUGCUUUUUUCUUUUUUAAAUGCAGAAUUUUAAGCCUCAACUCCAAACCGUCCGUCAGAAUUUCCAAGAAUGGGUCUCAGGGAUUUGAAUUUUUAAAAAGUUCCCAAGUGAUUCUGCUGGUGCCCGAGUUCUAGCAUGCCUAAGACAUUUCCUUACCAGCUCGAGUGUUUCAUAAAAUAUGUUCAAUUCAAAGGUGGAUGGUUGUGGAAAAUUAUUCAAAACAGCUUCAACCUGAUGAAGUGUUUAGUUGUCCUUGAAGAAUCAUUUCAUUUGAGCCUUCAUGCUUUAAUACCUAUCCUUUUUUCUACUACCAAUUCUUCUGAACUUAGUAGCACUCCAAAUUGGCUCAUUCUCAAAUUUCCUUAUGACGCAUUCUGUGGUAAAGACUGCUAAUUUUAUAUCCAGCAGUCUUUAUAUUCUCCUCUUCUUCAGUAACCAAAAACUUGAUUUUUUUGGAGGGUGUACAGUGUGCCAUGCCAAAAGACAGUAUUUCCCAGCCUCCCCUUCUCCUGUUGAUGGGCUAGUGAGUUAAGCUCUAGUAAGUGAAAUGUGAAGGCUUGUGGAAAGGUUCUAGGGACUGACUUCUAUGGACAAUGUACCCUUUUUCUUUUUCUCUGUCCUUCUACAUACUGCUUGGAACAUGGACACAAUGGCUGAAGUCCAGCAGCCAUCUUGGAUUGUGAGGUAACGAUGAAGAUGGAAGCCAUGUGAUAUGGCUUGGAUGUUUUGUCCCCUGUAAAUCUCAUGUUGAAUUGUAAUCCCCCAUGUUAGAGGUGGGGCCUGGUGGGAGGUGUUUGGGUCAUGGGAGUAGAUCCCUCAUGAAUGGCUUGGUGCUCUCCCCAUAGUGAGUGAGUGAGUUCUUGUUCUAUUUCAUGUGAGAGCUGGUUGCUUAAAAGGGUCUGGCACCUCUGUUGCUCCUGCUCUUGCCAUGUGGCAUGCCUACUCCAUCUUUACCUUCUGCCAUGAGUAAAAGCUUCCUGAGGCCUCACUAGAAGCUGAGCAGAUGCUGGUGCCAUGCUUGCACAGCCUGCAGAACCGUGAGCCAAGUAAACCUCUUUUCUUUAUAAAUUACACAGCCUCAGGUAUUCCUUUACACCAAUGCCAAAUGGACUAGCACACCAUGCUCUAAGUAGGGCAUAAAGAAAGGAGCCUGGAUCCCUAAUGACUGCAGAGCCAUGAUCCCAGCCCUGGACUGCUUGCCUCCACACUUCUGUCUUAUUGGUUAAGCCAAAAUUAUUUUGGGUUUUCCGUUACAUGCUGCAGAACCUAACCUAAUGAAUACCCCUGCUCUCUGUUGGUUUCACAGUGUGUCUCCAACACCAUCUUGAAGGUGCAGUGACUUGCAUAUAGUAGGUGCUUGAUAUUUACCAAGUACCCCCUGUGGGUCAGGCCCUACUCUCACCCUAAGGAUACAGCAGGAAGCAAAGCAGAGGUGGAGAAGAUCCCACUAAACACACAGGCCGCUUGGAAUGUUGGGCCAUCUGUCCUUUUGACAUGAAUUUUCCCUGUAAUGGGGGUAGAGCUGGUAACUGUUGGAUCAUCUGAUUAUUGGAGACAGAAGUCCUGUCACUUGCCCCUGCUGUUAGGAGCUGGAACAGUGAACCAUGGAGCUGUAUUUCGGUGAAUAUCAACAUGUGCAGCAGGAAUAUGGGGUCCAUCUGAGACUCGCAAGUGAUGAUACCCAAAAAUCAAGGAGUUCCCAGAACUCCAAGGCAGGCUCCUACGGUGUCAGUAUUCGGGUCCAGGGAAUUGAUGGUCACCCCUAUAUUGUCCUGAAUAACACAGAACGGUGCCUAGCAGGCACAUCGUUUUCUGAAAAUGGGCCACCCUUUCCACCUCCAGUGAUAAAUAACCUGCCUCUACAUUCCAGCAAUGGUUCUGUGCCAAAGGAGAACAGUGAAGAACUUCAGCUUCCAGAAAACCCAUACGCCCAGCCUAGCCCAAUAAGAAACCUGAAACAGCCCCUGCUCCAUGAGGGCAAGAAUGGAGUUCUAGAUCGCAAAGACGGGUCUGUGAAGCCAUCUCACCUGCUGAACUUUCAGAGGCAUCCAGAGCUUUUGCAACCCUAUGACCCUGAAAAGAAUGAGUUGAAUUUACAAAAUCACCAGCCUUCUGAGAGUAAUUGGCUAAAAACGUUGACAGAAGAAGGCAUCAACAAUAAGAAGCCUUGGACUUGCUUUCCCAAACCUAGCAAUUCCCAGCCUACCAGUCCCUCCUUGGAAGACCCGGCCAAAUCUGGUGUGACAGCUAUUCGUUUAUGCAGCUCCGUGGUCAUAGAGGACCCCAAAAAGCAGACCUCAGUGUGUGUAAACGUUCAGAGCUGCACCAAGGAGAGGGUGGGAGAGGAGGCCCUUUUCACUAGCGGGAGGCCCCUGACUGCCCACAGCCCACAUGCCCACCCUGAAACCAAGAAAACCAGGCCAGAUGUUCUUCCCUUCCGGCGACAGGAUUCAGCGGGACCCGUCCUGGAUGGAGCUCGGUCCCGGAGGUCCUCCUCGUCAUCCACAACUCCCACGUCAGCCAACUCUUUGUACAGGUUUUUACUGGAUGAUCAGGAAUGUGCCAUCCAUGCCGACAACGUCAAUCGUCAUGAAAACAGAAGGUAUAUUCCCUUCCUGCCAGGAACUGGACGGGAUAUUGAUACAGGAUCAAUUCCUGGUGUGGAUCAGUUAAUUGAAAAAUUUGAUCAAAAACCUGGGCUUCAGAGAAGAGGAAGGUCUGGGAAGCGAAACAGAAUUAAUACAGAUGACAGGAAAAGAUCCAGAAGCGUGGAUAGCGCCUUUCCUUUUGGCCUCCAAGGGAACUCGGAGUACCUGAUUGAAUUCAGUAGGAACUUGGGCAAGUCAAGCGAACACCUCCUCCGGCCUUCCCAGGUGUGCCCGCAGCGGCCACUGUCUCAGGAGCGCCGUGGGAAACAGAGCGUGGGCCGCACCUUUGCAAAGCUGCAGGGAGCAGCGCACGGGGCUUCAUGUGCCCACUCCAGGCCUCCCCAGCCGAACAUAGAUGGGAAAGUUCUGGAAACCGAAGGUAGUCAGGAAAGUACAGUGAUCCGUGCGCCCUCCCUUGGUGCACAGAGUAAAAAGGAGGAGGAGGUGAAAACAGCCACCGCUACGCUGAUGUUACAGAACCGGGCAACAGCAACUUCGCCUGAUUCUGGUGCCAAGAAAAUUUCCGUGAAGACAUUUCCUUCGGCCUCAAAUACUCAGGCCACACCGGAUCUCUUAAAGGGCCAGCAAGAGCUCACUCAGCAAACCAAUGAGGAGACAGCUAAGCAGAUUCUCUACAAUUACCUCAAAGAAGGAAGCACUGAUAAUGACGAUGCUACUAAAAGGAAAGUCAACUUGGUCUUUGAGAAAAUCCAGACCUUAAAGUCUCGAGCAGCUGGGAGCGCCCAAGGAAAUAACCAAGCUUGUAAUUCCACAUCUGAAGUCAAAGAUCUAUUGGAACAGAAAAGCAAGUUGACCAUAGAAGUGGCUGAACUUCAGAGACAGCUUCAACUGGAAGUCAAGAAUCAACAGAACAUUAAAGAAGAGAGAGAGAGGAUGAGAGCAAACCUAGAAGAGCUCCGAAGCCAACACAACGAAAAGGUGGAGGAGAACUCCACAUUGCAGCAACGACUGGAAGAAAGUGAAGGGGAGCUCCGGAAGAAUCUGGAGGAGCUAUUCCAGGUGAAGAUGGAACGGGAGCAGCAUCAGACUGAGAUCAGGGAUCUCCAGGACCAGCUCUCAGAAAUGCACGAUGAACUGGACAGUGCAAAGCGAUCGGAGGACAGGGAGAAGGGAGCUCUGAUUGAGGAGCUCUUACAGGCAAAACAGGAUCUUCAAGAUCUGCUGAUUGCCAAAGAGGAGCAAGAAGACCUCUUGAGAAAGCGAGAGCGUGAACUCACCGCCCUGAAGGGAGCCCUGAAAGAAGAGGUUUCCAGCCAUGAUCAGGAGAUGGACAAGCUGAAGGAGCAAUAUGAUGCUGAGUUGCAGGCCCUGAGGGAGAGUGUGGAAGAAGCAACCAAGAAUGUCGAGGUCUUGGCGAGCAGGAGCAACACUUCAGAGCAAGACCAGGCGGGGACUGAAAUGCGCGUGAAGCUUCUGCAGGAGGAGAAUGAGAAGCUGCAGGGAAGAAGCGAAGAGCUGGAGCGGAGAGUUGCUCAGCUUCAAAGGCAGAUCGAGGACCUGAAAGGCGAUGAAGCCAAGGCGAAGGAAACGCUGAAGAAGUACGAGGGAGAAAUACGACAGUUAGAGGAGGCCCUUGUGCACGCCAGAAAGGAAGAAAAAGAAGCUGUGUCAGCCAGAAGGGCCCUGGAGAAUGAACUGGAGGCUGCUCAGGGAAAUCUGAGUCAGACUACCCAGGAGCAGAAGCAGUUGUCUGAGAAGCUCAAAGAGGAGAGUGAGCAGAAGGAGCAGCUAAGAAGGUUGAAGAACGAGAUGGAGAAUGAGCGGUGGCACCUGGGCAAAACCAUUGAGAAACUGCAGAAGGAGAUGGCAGACAUUGUUGAGGCCUCCCGUACCUCAACCCUGGAGCUCCAGAACCAGCUGGAUGAGUAUAAGGAGAAAAACCGCAGGGAGCUCGCAGAAAUGCAAAGACAGUUGAAGGAGAAAACGCUGGAGGCAGAAAAGUCCCGACUGACAGCCAUGAAAAUGCAGGAUGAGAUGCGUCUGAUGGAGGAAGAGUUACGGGACUACCAGAGAGCUCAGGAUGAAGCACUCACAAAAAGGCAGCUUCUGGAGCAGACGCUGAAGGACCUGGAGUAUGAGCUGGAAGCCAAGAGUCACCUCAAAGAUGACCGCAGCAGGCUGGUCAAGCAGAUGGAGGACAAGGUGUCUCAACUGGAGAUGGAACUGGAAGAAGAGAGAAACAACUCAGAUUUGCUGUCUGAGAGGAUCAGUAGGAGCAGGGAACAGAUGGAGCAGUUGAGGAAUGAGCUACUUCAGGAGAGAGCUGCGAGACAAGACUUGGAGUGCGACAAGAUUUCCCUGGAGAGGCAGAACAAGGACUUAAAGAGCCGGAUUAUCCACCUGGAAGGUUCCUACAGGUCCAGCAAAGAGGGGCUGGUUGUGCAGAUGGAGGCCAGGAUCGCGGAGCUGGAGGACCGCCUGGAGAGUGAGGAGAGGGAUCGGGCCAAUCUUCAGCUCAGCAACCGGCGGCUGGAGCGGAAAGUGAAGGAGCUGGUGAUGCAGGUGGAUGAUGAGCACCUGUCAUUGACUGAUCAGAAGGACCAGCUGAGCUUGCGUUUGAAAGCCAUGAAGCGGCAGGUGGAGGAGGCUGAGGAGGAAAUCGACAGACUGGAAAGUUCUAAAAAGAAGCUGCAGAGGGAGCUGGAGGAGCAGAUGGACAUGAAUGAGCAUCUGCAGGGGCAGCUCAACUCCAUGAAGAAGGACUUAAGCAGACUGAAGAAGCUGCCGAGUAAAGUGCUGGAUGACAUGGAUGACGACGAUGACCUCAGCACGGAUGGGGGAAGCCUCUAUGAGGCGCCUGUGAGCUACACAUUCUCCAAGGACAGCACCGUCGCCAGCCAGAUCUGAGUGCUCUCCCGGGCUGUGGAAGUACCUGUCAUUCCUGCAGGAGCUGCAGCCACCCAAAGUGGGAGGCAGGGAGGGGAGCAUCUGUCUGCCACUGAGACCAAUCACAGCCUCUUUGCACAGCAUGCCAGCUCCUCAGUGUUACAUUCCUCGCCAGGGUCUCUCAGUGGGUCUUCGACAGAGAGCUUUUGCAGUUUAAAAUGUUGGGAUGCCUGAGGACCAGGAGCCACCACCCACUGGGGUGUUGUGAGAGAUACACUUUGGUAGGCUGAGGCCCCUGUUCCACAGCCACUAUUUGCAUUGCUGUCCCUGCCCCCUCAUCACUCCCCCUGCCAAGACAAAGGGUCCAGAAGGCUAGGACUUACUUAAUAGCACUGUGCAGGGAGGAAACCAUGUAUAGCUUGUACAUAUUUUAAACCAGACCUUCUCACGAACUGCUGCUGUUGGGUUUGGAAUGUGAUGGAGGCUUGGUAGGGUGGCUGGUUUGUAAAGUUCAUGCAUCUAUAUUGAGUAUUCUUUUUUUUUUUUUUUGAGAUGGAGUUUCAUUCUUGUUGCCGAGGCUGGAGUGCAAUGGCGCAACCUUGGCUCACUGCAACCUCUGCCUCCCUGGUUCAAGUGAUUCUCCUGCCUCAUCCUCCCAAGAAGCUGAGAUUACAGAUGACCACCACCACUCCUGGCUAAUUUUUUGUAUUUAGUAGAGACGGGGUUUCACCAUGUUGGUCAGGCUGGUCUUGAACUCCUGACCUCAGGUGAUCCACCUGCCUCAGCCUCCCAAAGUGCUGAGAUUACAGGCAUGAGCCACCACGCCCAGCCAUUGAGUAUUCUUUUUUAAAAUAUGAAGCUAUUAGAUUUUAAGUGUUGAGGAGCAGAGGUGAGAAGAGAGAGAGAGAGAGAAAGUCAAAUAAAGUCAAAGACCAGUUUGGAAACCAAAGUUGGAAAAGAAGAAUUGUAGUGGUCAUGGACAGCUAAGACUGAGCAUAGCAGUUCACAUGGUCUGGGUAAACAAGUCACUGGCACAGGGGAAAGCCAGAAGGUUGCUUGUGUCUGUGACUGCAGCUAUGGCCUUGUUUGCUUAGUUUAUCUGGAAUUCUGUUAUAAUUUCUGAACUGUUCUGAGACCUGUUCCCAGUCACUGAUUGCAAUUUCUUUUACACAGGUUGGGUAGGGAGAGUUGUAGGUAAGGCCUUAAACAAAUGAGGCCGUUUCUGGAAGGAUAGGGCUGUGUGGUCAUGUCCCACAGCAAGCUUUUGGGAUCGGGGGAAUAAGAGGGUAUGGGGGAAAGGUUCAUAGACUUAGGUGUGAGAAUGAGGUGGGAGGUGUCUGGUAAGGUCAUGGGGGAAGGGAGAUGAGAGAGGAGAUAGGCAGAUGUGGGUAUGGGGCCCAGUGUGAGAAGGAAGACAGAGAAGUUCUUGAAAGCUGGGGGAUGUGUGGGCAAGAGGUGGAUUGAGCAGGAUCUCAGGGUUAUGUCGAGGAAGGGAAGAAAGAAACAGAAGUCAGGCAGAGGCGUGUCUGUGCAAACUGGAGGACUCCUUCCAACUUCCUGGAACAAAGCGACAUCGCCAGCAGCAGGCUGGCAGGGAGUGGUUGAGGUCUGGGGGCCAGGCCACAUGGCUGGAGAGGAAUUUCAGGGAGCAUAGCAUCGGGAGGAUGCUACAUAUCCAGGGACUCCCUCCUGGCCUUCCUGUGUCACUUCACAAUGUGACAGUCCCCAGGCAUGCCCACAGGCCAGGCCCAGUCACAGCUGGGCUUCCACAGGUCAGAAUAUGGGACAGGACAUGGUCAGGGAGAGGACCCUGUGAGUUGGUGACAUAUAUGUGGCAGAGAUGGUAGUGUUCAGCUGCUUCAGCAGUGUCCCCAACCAUCCCAAUAGGGUGGGGGCCUGUGGGCCAGAGGACUCCAUGACAGUAGCCAUGGAGUCCCACCUGUGCCAGGUCAGAGCCCACCCGGCAGGUUUCAGAGUGGUCAGCCCAGUUUAAGGGUGGGAGUCUGGAGCCAGACAGCCAAGCCCCUUCCACAUCUACAGGGUCACUGUCAUCCUCACCACAGCCAGGGGUGAUUCUCACCUCUGCCUGCUUAUGUGGGGUGUGGCCGAUUCCUCCCUUUAGUCAUUCAUUCAUUUAGCACAUAUUUAUUGGGCAUCGGUGAUGUGUCAGGCACAGUCCUUGGCACACAGAAUACAGCAGUGAAUUAAACAGGCAAAAAUUCCUCCCCUCCUGGAGCUCAGUGUCAGGAAAGGGGGUGAUAAAUGACAAUCAAAUCGACAUGGAGGUUGAGCACCUCUGUACUCAGCCCUCUGUCUGUCCUUCUGAGGACGCAACAAGCCUGGUUCCCUAGAGCUCACUUUGACCCUCAAUAUGUUCAUAAUUUCCCUGCUGCUUCUCCCAUCGUUAGACAUCUGCCAGUAAGCCUGCUGAGAGAAGCCUCAGCCCACUCAUACCUAGAGACGCUGCUGGGGAAGGUCAGCACACCCAAGAACUUUGGGAGUGUGUGUCUGUUUUGGUUUGUGAGAAAGUAGCUGCCCCUCAUUCUGGCCAGUUCUUUCCAGUAGCCAUGGGGCUGGCUACAAGAAGCAAAACUGCCCAUGCAAAGAGAACACAGGUCACUUUUCAAAACACUUGCAUCAUUACCCUAAAAAUAGGCUGUUAUGCGUUUUGACAAUUGCGCUAUCCUACACUCUGAGGGAGUUGGCAACGCAUGCGGUAUAGUGGAGUGGGAAGAGUUGAGACUGAAAGUUAAGAGAAGGGUUUUCAAGUCCCGGCUCAUCUCACCCCAGUGACUUUGACAGUGUGCUCACUCUCAGAGCCAUGGAUUACCUGGAACAAAGUGCAGAUUAGUGCCCACGGUCCUUUCCAGGUAUAACAUGCUAUCGUUCUUUAAUUUUAUUAUAUAUACAUACUUUUCUUCUGUUUUUUGCUUUAAGAACUAACCCCGAUCAAGAGUAUUUUCUUUAGCUAGCUUAAAAAGAAAACAUAUAUUUUAUGUAAAAACACAUACAUGGCCAAAUGCAAUACUGAAGAGACAAUCAUCCUGUAUCUUUUAUGGUUUUUCCUGCUUCUGAGUGUCGUUCUACAAUGCCCGUUGACUUAUUCCAUUGCGUCUCUGCUUUAGGGUAUGGUUUGGUCGCUUUGGUUGUCAUGAGAAAGAGACAUUCUCCUUGCAGCUACCUCCAUGUGAGUGAAUUCCUGGAUAAAGCAAGAUUUCCUUUCAAUAAACGCUGUCACCCAAUGGGAA